GGAGCUGCGCGGGGAGCGCUCGCUGGCUGGCUGGCUGGCUGGCUCUCCGCUGCGCUGCGCUGCGCUCCGGCCGCUCCCGCGGCCCGUGGAUGGGGGUGUCCGGCUGAGCCCCGGGAUCCGCCUCCCUCCGCCAGGACCCGCACAGGUGCCGUCGCGGGGGUUGACUUUAGUUAGGACCCGACUCACUGCUGGGGGUGGGGUCUGGUGGGGGUGGUAAGGAGGCCCCGGGAUUCUCUGACAGGACGGUCUGGGGUCGCCGCAGCUCCCCUCACCUGGUCCCAUUCUGGGAUUAGAAAGGAACAACGGGAGGCCGUCGCCUUCCUGCCCAGCCCUUCAGGGAGCGCAGCUGGGACGCCGCGCCAGGCCCUGGAGAUGUGGGAUGAUGGGCACUUCCAGUAUCAUCUCAGCAUCGGCCCUCCAGCCAGGCCUGAUAAACUCAUCCUGAAAGUCGCUGUUGUUCUCCUGCUGAGCAAGAAUGGAGGCCCCACUGGUGAGUCUGGAUGAAGAGUUUGAGGACCUUCGACCCUCCUGCUCGGAGGACCCGGAGGAGAAGCCCCAGUGUUUCUAUGGUUCAUCUCCCCACCAUCUCGAGGACCCCUCCCUCUCCGAGCUUGAGAAUUUUUCUUCCGAAAUAAUCAGCUUCAAGUCCAUGGAGGACCUCGUAAAUGAAUUUGAUGAGAAGCUCAAUGUCUGCUUUCGGAACUACAACGCCAAGACCGAGAACCUAGCUCCCGUGAAGAACCAGUUACAGAUCCAAGAGGAGGAGGAGACCCUUCAGGACGAGGAGGUUUGGGAUGCUCUGACAGACAAUUACAUCCCUUCACUCUCAGAAGACUGGAGGGAUCCAAACAUCGAGGCUCUGAAUGGCAACUGCUCUGACACUGAGAUCCAUGAGAAAGAAGAGGAAGAGUUCAAUGAGAAGAGUGAAAAUGAUUCCGGUAUCAACGAGGAGCCUCUGCUCACAGCAGAUCAGGUAAUUGAGGAGAUUGAGGAAAUGAUGCAGAACUCCCCAGACCCUGAGGAAGAAGAGGAGGUUCUGGAAGAAGAGGAUGGAGGAGAAACUUCCUCCCAGGCAGACUCGGUCCUCCUGCAGGAGAUGCAGGCAUUGACACAGACCUUCAACAACAACUGGUCCUAUGAAGGGCUGAGGCACAUGUCUGGGUCUGAGCUGACCGAGCUGCUGGACCAGGUGGAGGGUGCCAUCCGUGACUUCUCGGAGGAGCUGGUGCAGCAGCUGGCCCGCCGGGACGAGCUGGAGUUUGAGAAGGAAGUGAAGAACUCCUUUAUCACGGUGCUUAUUGAGGUUCAGAACAAGCAGAAGGAGCAGCGAGAACUGAUGAAAAAGAGGCGGAAAGAGAAAGGGCUGAGCCUGCAGAGCAGCCGGAUAGAGAAGGGAAACCAGAUGCCUCUCAAGCGCUUCAGCAUGGAAGGCAUCUCCAACAUUCUGCAGAGUGGCAUCCGCCAGACCUUUGGCUCCUCAGGAACUGACAAACAGUAUCUGAACACAGUCAUUCCUUACGAGAAGAAAGCCUCUCCUCCCUCAGUGGAAGACCUGCAGAUGCUGACAAACAUUCUCUUUGCCAUGAAGGAGGAUAAUGAGAAGGUGCCUACUUUGCUAACGGACUACAUUUUAAAAGUGCUCUGCCCUACCUAACCUUGCCCUUUGGAGCAGCCUCGCUGCAGGAGGUCACUGAGCAAGAGUCAUUCCAUCACAGGGACUGCAUGAGACCAUGUAACCUCCGACAUGUAUUUAAACGUGUAUAGCUUAACCUGGAUUAAACACGAGCAAGCGCGCGGGGUCCUUUGCCGUUGGCUUCUAGUGCUAGUAAUCAUUGGAUGCAUGAUGGGGCAGGGCCGGUGAUGGUGCCUCCCCCUUGCUGGUGUCAGGAGAGGGGAAGGCAGCCGCUUUCACCGCUCAUUAUGUAGUCUGGCUACAGCCCUCAAAAACAGCUUAUACUCUUAAGACUAAUUUUGAAAUAAAACCUUCAUUUAAUUAAUAUUCUUCAUGUGCUUUGGAGUGUGAUGUCCAUUAGCCCUCUGCUCCAGACUCCAGAGACGGGCUGUAUAGCAUUCUUUGCACGCCGGCCUGUGGCCUGUGGCAGCCAGUGCUGUGUUUAGGGACCGGGCGCAUGUCCUGUUGUGGGUCGUGGUGGGAUCAUGGGACACAGUGGGGCUGCAUACAGCAUAGGCAGAAGGAGACCCUCUGCAACCUCAGUUUUUGCUGCUCAGCCACAUGCAAGGGAGCUGCACCAGGGGCUGCAGAAAGGAGCUGGUCAGAGUGGGUGAGACGGGGGUGAGAGUGUGCAAUUAGCAGAUAGAAAGUGGGCCUCAUGGAGGAGCCACACAGCUGCAGAUCUCCUGGUGGGAUGGCCAGGCUGGCCCUGGAGACCCUCCCCAGGCUGUCCACGGGGACCUGGAGGCUCAGGGCCUGCGGGAAGUCAGCUCUGCUGAGCUUUCCCAACGUAGGGGACUGCAACUUGUUUCCUGUACUUGACGAAACCACCACUCCCUGUUUGUCCCCAACGACCCCUGGCAACAGUGUCCUUUGACUUUGCAGUGCUGUCCUGGCCCUUCCCGCGGCCCUCCAUGAACAGCAGCUCUGACUCCUCGCACUGUCUCCAGCAUUGAUGGCAGGCAGCUGCCAGCCUUGACCAACCAGCAGGCGAAGGUCUCCUCGUAUCCCGGAUGCUGGCUCGAUCUCACCACAGUCUGAAUUCUGUUGGCUUCCGUCUUCUGGCUUGAAAGACAUUGAGCCUGCCAAUUCCCAUAUCCUCCUCUGAAAGCAAAAACUUGUACUGGGCACUUGCUGUAGCCUGCACUGGCUUCAUCGUGCAUUAGCACACAUCACAGCAUCACCACGUGUAAACAGGUGCUAGUAUGAUCCCGAUUUUGCAGAGGAGGAAACCAAGCAGCAGAGAUGUUCAGUAGCUCGCCCAAGGCUGUGUAGGAAGUGGUAGAGUCAGGCUGGCAUUUAGGUUUCUUAUCCAGUGAGACUUCCAUUGAUUCCCAGGAGUUUAGUGUCUGCUUGAACUAAGCAUGCCACAGAGAAAGCCAUACUUUAUCACAUCAGCAGCUCCACAGAAGGCCACAGAAUCCAUCUAGGGGACACAGAAGGCACUCCCAGUGCCCUGCCUCCCUUCCUGGGCCUCUGCUUUUUUUUUUUCAGACGGAGUUUGACUCUUGUUGCUCAGGCUGGAGUACAAUGGCGCUAUCUCAGCUCGCCGCAAACUCCGCCUCCCACGUUCAAGUGAUUCUCCUGCCUCAGCCUCCCGAGUAGCUGGGAUUACAGGCAUGCAGCACCACACCCAGCUAAUUUUAUAUUUUUAGUAGAGACCAGGUUUCUACAUGUUGGUCAGGUUGGUCUCGAACUCCCGACCUCAGGCGAUCUGCCCUCCUAGGCUUCCCAAAGUGCUGGGAUUAUAGGCGUGAGUCACCGCGCCUAGCUCGGCUUCUGCUUUUCCAGAAGCAGAACACUAGCAAUCUUAGCUAGGGGUGGCGGAGACUUAUCCCCCCAGGAAAACUGCUGCAAUGCCUAAAGCUCUAGUCCAGGCAUCUGCCCAGAGCAGAGCUUCUCCAUAGAUAGAGCCCCGGCUGCCACAGGAGCAUGGAAGUGACAACUCGUCCUGUGAUAAAAGGGCAUGGAUUCAGUUCGGCAGUUCACUGGUGCUAAGGCUGAACAUGCCCAGGGUCAUUAGUGGUGUGAGGUCAUUAGCAUGUUUAGCACUCUGCCGGCGACGGGGUUUUUCACCAGCCUCAGCAAAGGGGAAGCAGUGAAUUCCUGAGAGCUUUUCUUCCUGCCUUGGAUUUGUCAGAUCUGGGUCAGCCACUCCUUUCCCCCAAUUUAUCCUGCCAGCAGGUGUCUGAAGCGGCAGAGACAAGCUAAUCAAAGCUGCUGGGAGUUAAAAAUAAAUCUCGAGUGUUGGGGAUACACUCUGGCUAGGAGGAGGUGAGCAGGGCAGGCUGAAAACAGUGGCUCCUCCUUUCUCUCUUGUUUGUCCGUCUAUCAGGAGUUUAAGGGGAAUAUGAAAUCAAUUCCUCAUGGUUUUGCAUUGCCCUUCCCUGUGUUCUUCCUAUUCAAAGUGUGCUUUCCAGGCCAGCAGCACUGACCGCACUUAGAAGCUUGUUAGAAAUGCAAAAUCUCAGGCCCCACAUCAGGCCUACUAAGUCAGAAUUUGCAUUUUAACAAGGUCUCCCUUUAAAAGGGAGGCAGCUCUUCUCUUAAAAGGAGCCUGGGUUUUGUGCCUUGAGUUCAAAUGCAGCUCUACUACGUAUUAAGCUAAAUCUCCCUGCAACUUGUAUUUGCAUCAAGGAUUAGAGAAACUCUGCCCUAGGUUUUCAGAGUUGCUGAAUCCUUGACUCUUCAAUGCUGAACCUAGGGAAUUUGUGGCUAGUGUGAUUAUCAGGUGAACCCAAUUGUCUUCCCUCAGCUUUUCCCUCUUCUGGUCUUUCUGGAUUGUAGAAACCUCACAGAAGAGUCCCAAGAAUUAACUGAUUUUCAGGCCUGAGUCAAUCCUGAUUGCAAAACUCAAGUCCUGUCUAGGAUGUCCGCACUCCGCAAAGUGUGCCAGAGAGCCACGGUCUGCAGGGAGCCCUCCUAGGUAGGUCAGAGGUCUGUCUGGCAAAUACAGCCUAUAAAUGAGGUAUGUUUCCAUCAAUUAAAGGAUUUUGCUAGGCCUAGUCUGGUCAAGUUCUGGUAAGAAAACUCCACCACAGGGCCGGGCGUGGUGGCUCAUGCCUGUAAUCCCAGAACUUUGGGAGGCCGAGGUGGGCAGAUCACCUGAGGUCAGGAGUUUGAGACCAGCCUGGCCAACAUGGUGAAACCCCCUCUCUACUGAAAAUACAAAAAUUAGCCAGCUGUAGUGGUGCAC